GACCCUCCCUGCAGAACACACAGAGGAACUCGGCAUCGUUCUCGCAGAAGAAGUAGAUCUUCUCGCCGUGCUCCUCGCAGGUGGAGAACAGAGCACACCAUGAGGUCACAGGGGGAUGGGUUUCCUGGAAUCUGUAGACCACAGUGGCUGGGGAGAACUGGGGAGCAGAAGCUUCCUGUCAGAUUGAGCAGGUGGGAGCCAUAAACUUCUGGCUCUGAGGCGUGCCCACAGCAUCAAAGUCCAGGCUGGAGUGAGAGGUGUGGACUUCGGGAGAUUCUGCCGGAAGUGUGUGGGCGGGACGCUGUUUCGACACUGCAGGUAGGGUGUAAGGAUUGCUCAUCGGGUCCCCUCUUCUGCUCUCCUUUCCUCCCUCACCACAUCUGCCCAUGGUGGCCCCUCCUACGGUCCCAAAUCCCCCACCACCUGGCACAACAGUCCCCUUUGGGGUUCGGGUAACACUGGACUAUUUUAUUUAUUUAUUUAUUUAUUUAUUUAUUUAUUUAUUUAUUUAUUUUUACUGUAGCGGGGAGAAGGCAAGAAACCAUAAUGCAAAUGAUUUAUGUUGAUACACAUUAGAAAACGAUUAGUCAGAUAAUCAGUUUCAACCACAUUUAUCUAGGGUUUAGUAUUUUUAUAUUACUACAUUCAAUUUUAAUAACCCUCUAGGCAAACAUUAUUACCUUCAUUUUACAGAGAAAGAAAUGUAAACUGACUUUCCAAAUGUAAAGUGACUUUCCAAAGGUCACAAAGCUAGAAAGUAUCACGUUAAGGACGAUCCCAGUCUCCUGGCUUAAAGCCCUACGCUCCUCCCACACCUCAUGCCAAGACCAAGAUCUGCAGCCACGGUCCUUCACCCAUGCACACAUCUGUGGAUAAAACCAGGCCUUCCCCCAUUCUCCCACUGGGUGAUCAGCCUAGCCCCUUGUGGUUGCUCCCUUUUUACUCUAAUCACUUUAUUACCUCCCCUUCCCAUCCAAUCUCUGCUCUUCCUGCCACGAGUGCAGCCCAGGAACUAGUUUGUCCAAUACAGGAGCCACCAGCCACAUGUGUCUACUGAGCACUGAAAUGUGGCCGGUCUGAAUGGCGGCAUGCUGUAUAUGUAAAAUACAUACCGGAUUUCUUUUUUUUCUUUUUCUUUUUCUCUUUUUUCUUUUCUUUUUUUUUUUUUUUGAAAUGGAGUCUCGCUCUGUCUCCCGGGAUGGAGUGCAGUAGCGCGAUCUUGGCUCACUGCAAGCUCCUCCUCCCGGGUUCACACCAUUCUCCUGCCUCAGCCUCCCGAGUAGCUGGGACUACAGGCGCCGGCCAGCACGCCAGGCUAAUUUUUUUGUAUUUUUAGUAGAGACGGGGUUUCACCGUGUUAACCAGGAUGGUCUAGAUUUCCUGACCUCGUGAUCCGCCCGCCUAGGCCUCCCAAAGUGCUGGGAUUACAGGCGUGAGCCACCGCGCCCGGCCAACACACCGGAUUUCAAAGGCUUUUCACAAAUUUAAAAAUGUAAAAUAUCUUAUUAAUGACUUUUUAUAUGGAUCACAUAUUGAAAUGAUAAUAUUUUGGAAAUAUAGGACUAAAUAAAAUAACAUCAUUAAAAUUACUUUCACCUGUUUAGACUAUUUUUAUAUGGCCACUAGGAAAUUUUAAAUUGCAUAUGUGGCUCACUUUGCGUUUAUGUUGAAUAGCAUUGCUCGGAAGACAGAUCUGACAGCAAAUUAUUUAUGGUCACUCACCUUCUUACUUGUGUGCCUAGGGCAAGCUGAAUAACCUGGCUGGGCCUCAGCUUUCUCAUUUAUGAAAUGGAGAUCCUAAUAGCACUGAUGUUGCAGAGCAGACACAGAAAUAAGAUCAUACUUUUAAAUUGCUUGUAUCAAUGUAAGUUGUACCGUCAUUGUAAAUAAAUUCUGGCCAAAUUGCUUGUAUCAAUGUAAGUUGUACCGUCAUUGUAAAUAAAUUCUGGCCGUUAGUAGUUUUCUUUCUCCUCCCCAUCAUAGGGAAUAUUCCAGCCUCUUUUGAGGCCUGCAGCAGGCCAGUUGAGGCAUCACCAUUGAAGUUGCUGGUGCAGUGUACACCCUGGCACAAGGACCUUAUCUGAGCCCCCACACUCUCCUGCUUGCUGAUGGGCAAGCCCUGGGCUGGCUGAUACCUCCAAUCUCUUUGGAGACAGCUGGCCAUAUGGCAGAAAGGCUGGAAUGGCAUCUCCACUCUGUGACCCAGUCUCCCACUUGCCCCCAAAAGAAUAUUUCUUCUGACAGUGGACAGCUGACAUAUCACCACUUUCCUUCUACUGGUACCCUGAGGGAGCCGGUCACUAUCGACUGCGGCCACAACUUCUGCCGGGCCUGCCUUACCCGCUACUGUGAGAUACCAGGCCCAGACCUGGAGGAGUCCCCUACUUGCCCACUCUGCAAAGAACCCUUCCGUCCUGGGAGCUUCCGGCCCAACUGGCAGCUGGCUAACGUGGUGGAGAACAUUGAGCGCCUCCAGCUGGUGUCCACACUGGGUUUGGGAGAGGAGGAUGUCUGCCAAGAGCACGGAGAGAAGAUCUACUUCUUCUGUGAGGAUGAUGAGAUGCAGUUGUGCGUGGUGUGCCGGGAGGCUGGGGAGCACGCUACCCACACCAUGCGCUUCCUGGAGGAUGCAGCGGCUCCCUAUAGGGAACAAAUCCAUAAGUGUCUUAAAUGUCUAAGAAAAGAGAGAGAGGAGAUUCAAGAAAUCCAGUCAAGAGAAAAUAAAAGGAUGCAAGUCCUCCUGACUCAGGUGUCCACCAAGAGACAACAGGUGAUUUCUGAGUUCGCACACCUGAGGAAGUUUCUAGAGGAACAGCAGAGCAUCCUCUUAGCACAAUUGGAGAGCCAGGAUGGGGACAUCUUGAGGCAACGGGAUGAAUUUGAUUUGCUGGUUGCUGGGGAGAUCUGCCGGUUUAGUGCUCUUAUUGAAGAACUGGAGGAGAAGAAUGAGAGGCCAGCAAGGGAGCUCCUGACGGACAUCAGAAGCACUCUAAUAAGAUGUGAAACCAGAAAGUGCCGGAAACCGGUGGCUGUGUCGCCAGAGCUGGGCCAGAGGAUUCGGGACUUUCCCCAGCAGGCCCUCCCGCUGCAGAGGGAGAUGAAGAUGUUUCUGGAAAAACUAUGCUUUGAGUUGGACUAUGAGCCAGCUCACAUUUCUCUAGACCCUCAGACUUCCCACCCCAAGCUCCUCUUGUCCGAGGACCACCAGCGAGCUCAGUUCUCCUACAAAUGGCAGAACUCACCAGACAACCCCCAACGUUUUGACCGGGCCACCUGUGUUCUGGCCCACACUGGCAUCACAGGGGGGAGACACACGUGGGUGGUGAGUAUAGACCUGGCCCAUGGGGGCAGCUGCACCGUGGGCGUGGUGAGCGAGGAUGUGCAGCGGAAGGGGGAGCUUCGGCUGCGGCCAGAGGAGGGGGUGUGGGCUGUGAGGCUGGCUUGGGGCUUCGUCUCGGCUCUGGGCUCCUUCCCCACACGGCUGACCCUGAAGGAGCAGCCCCGGCAGGUGAGGGUGUCUCUUGACUAUGAGGUGGGCUGGGUGACCUUCACCAACGCUGUCACCCGAGAGCCCAUCUACACCUUCACUGCCUCCUUCACUAGGAAGGUCAUUCCCUUCUUUGGGCUCUGGGGCCGAGGGUCCAGUUUCUCCCUGAGCUCCUGAGAAGGAGCAGUUACCUACUCUCCUCUAAGUACAGGACUCAUAUCAACCCAAGUACCAUGUGGACUUGAUCCCUGGCUGAAUCACCUGGAUGACUUGGAAUAGAAAUGACUGCUUUAGAAGAUGGGAUGGGGCCGGGUGGUAAGGGAUAGAAGAGAGGACUCUCAAUCUACUGAUCAAGUCCUUUCCCCAAUGCCCAGUGGAUGGCCAGGGUACCUGGGGACUCAGGCUGCUGCCAGUUCUGCUCACCACCAUCCGUGCUUGGCACAGAAGUAGCUGCAUAGAAAGGGCACUGGAUUUGAAGUCAGAAGACCUGGGUUCUUGAACCAGCCUGUCAACCAGUUGUAUGACUUUAAACAAGGCAUCUCACCUCUUUUCAUCUUGUUUUCUUCCAAUAAUGUUAGAGUUCAUGUAAUCACAUUCUCUAGAACCAUUUAGUUUGUGUUAACUAUGAACCAAGCAGUGUGGUGGCCACUGGUGACUUGAAAAUAUAGAGAAAAAAAAAACCUGCUCUAUAUCUGAAAGAGCUCUUGGGAAGACAGAGAAACAUAAAGAGGAAAUUACAGCACAGUGUGGUGGGUGUUACGGGAAGUCCAACCCCAGCAUUAUGGGAGUUCAGGGGAAGGGGCAUAGCCCAGCCUGGAAGGAGAGGGUGAGUGGGGGAUGGCUUUCUGAAAAGGGUGGUCUAAAGGAUGCCUAUGGUCAAUAGGGAAAAGAGGGGAAGAAGCAUCUUAAGAAGAGGAAACAGCAGAGAACUGGCUGGAUGACCUGUGACUCUGGAGCACUGGGUUGUCUCCAUUGUCAUUAUGGGCAGAUGUGUGCCAUCCCCAGCCGACGCCACUCACUGCCUCCUUCCUCCUGGUGUUGCCACUUCUGGGUGAGAUUAAGGUGCAGGGCCUGGGGGCAGGAGGACAUAAGGUAUAGCCAUAAAUCAUAACCCAGGGACCACACUCAACCCUAGGGAAAUUGUCUUCCUGAUCAGUUGAUUACCAUCUGAGGUCAAGAAAUGAGAUAGUGGGAGCAAAUGGGUCACAAAUAGCUCAGCUGUGGGCUCAGAAACUGCUAGGUAAAAGAAUUCCAGAAGGAGGCCAGGGCAUAAGUUGGAUGACCUAUGAACUUUAGUCUAAAGAAUUGAGACUACCGUAAUUGAGACUACUGUAGUGACAUCUGAGAAAUGGGAUGGAAGAGUGACCAUGUUUUAUUUUCUUGUUCUUGUCACUAUUGUAUUUUAUUUUGCAUAAUCAUGCCCUUCACUGACAGUCUCCUUAACAUCAUCUGUUUACUCUGCUCAGUGUAAACUACAAUGCUCUGUCAUCUCCCUACUGGGUCUCCUGGGAGGAGGGGAGCCAUCCAGGGUGCAAACUCAAAGGCAGAGGGCACAGCGUGCUUAGGCCCAAGCUUAGAAUUCAAUUGAGAAGUUCUGUUGUUCAUCCUUACCUCAGCAGGUAGAAAAGAGGUGGAGAUCAGAAGCCAGGGAUUAGAGAUUGAAUUGCUUUCCCUGGGAGUGUGCAGUAUCUCAUUAAAAUGUUGUAUAUUCAAAAAAAUACAGACACACACAAGUGCCUAUAUAAUGAUAAAACAUAUCCAAAGCACCCAAACCUGUGAUUCCAGAAAAGUAGAUCCUAUUUUUGUUUAUUUUUAUUGGCUUUAGCUGUGUCUUUUGAAAGGACUAUUAUCCUCUAAAAUGUAUGUGUAUGAAGAUCCUGGCUUGCAGCUCGGGAGCUUUACACACCUUGUGUCACUUUAUCUUGGUAACGAGCCAAGAUCAUGCAACCAGUUCAUCCAUGUCUGACCCAAGAGCUCUUAACUGCUAUGCUGCACUGCCUCAUUCAGAGAUAGAUGCCUGCAUGGGUCCUGGCGAUUAUUUUAAUGCUGGCUACACCCCCACAGGUGACUUGGAUUCAGAAAUACAAUUUAUAUUUCUUCUUUUUAAAUUGUUUUAUUUUAUUUUUCUUUUAAUAGUUAUAUGUCAGUGAGAACAAUUUAUAUGUCUUACACUGAGAAAUAAAACUGCUCAUAAGUGAAAACA